ACGGCUGUUUCCUGUCCUGGUGCAUGGUGGUCGGACGAAGGAAUUGUUGGAAAAUUUUCUCGGAGGUUCGUAUAUAAAUGUGUUUUUACCCAGUGUGCAUUAUUCUCCGCCUGGCCGCCGCCCUCAGCGCGGCGGCGCGGGCCCGCUUGGGCCCGGGCUCCGGCUCCCGCUGCUCAGCCUCCGCCGCAGGCCUUGCCGAUUUUAUGGGCCGGCCGCGGUAGCGGCGUCUGGGCAGAAGCGGAGUUUAUUAAUAACCCGCGGCCGCCACUCUAGGCGGCGGAGCUUUUUUCGUUGAGGACUCAACUCCCCCCAGCUUGUCUCUGAGCGAUGCGCCCCGCCUGUUUCCCUCAGGGGACCGCCAAGGGGAGGGAGUGAAAGAGGGGAGGGUGGAGCCCUCGGGAGCCUUGGCCGCGUUUCUCGGCCUGACCUCCGCGCAGAGCGAGUCCCCAGGCGCCGCCGAGGCAGAGUUCCGCCGCCUGGGACGCCGGGCCCACGGGCCACACCAGGCCGCAGCGGGGGCGCCGGGGACAGGGCUGGCCCAGGCCCUCCCAGGACCUGCCGGUCUCACCUAGCGCUUGCUUCCCAUGCGUAUCGUGGGCAGAUUGUUUCCCCCUCACCCUUUCUUCUAUUAAAAAAAAAAAAAGGUUACUGAGGUCUAACAUCGGAUAUUAGAAAUUUACAAUUUUAUCCUCCCUUUUCUCCAGUUUUGGCCAAAAGAGUGAACAAAUUCUUAUAAGUCUCUUUGAAACGUAUUAUUGUGGAACGCGAACUAGUUUUUAUUCCUUCCCCUUUUGCUUUGGACAUUUGUUUUUUCCACAUAAUAACGAAGUUAAAAAGAGGAAAGAAGAAUACCAUUGCCAGCCCAUUAUUUGUUUAAAAUCAGCGUCAGCCUUUGCUUUGGAAGUGUCUAAAUCAGCUGAUAUAAUCAAGUGAGAAUGUGGGGAGAAAUUGUAGGUUCGAGAUUGUGGUCGGCUUUGUCCUGAAUCUUACCAGAAGAUACUUGUGUUUUCCUGUAGUUGACAAAAAACGGUAGAAGAUGUUGUUAGCCCAAAUAAAUCGAGAUUCUCAGGGAAUGACAGAGUUUCCUGGAGGAGGGAUGGAGGCGCAACAUGUUACGCUGUGCUUGACAGAGGCAGUCACCGUGGCAGAUGGUGACAACUUAGAAAAUAUGGAAGGCGUAAGCUUGCAAGCAGUAACACUUGCAGAUGGUUCUACUGCUUACAUACAACACAAUUCUAAAGAUGCAAAACUCAUAGAUGGCCAGGUCAUUCAGUUGGAAGAUGGUUCUGCGGCCUAUGUUCAACAUGUACCCAUACCUAAAAGUACAGGGGACAGUUUGCGUCUAGAGGAUGGUCAAGCAGUACAGUUAGAAGAUGGUACCACAGCAUUUAUUCACCACACCUCCAAAGAUAGUUAUGACCAGAGUGCAUUACAGGCGGUUCAGCUGGAAGAUGGUACCACAGCUUAUAUCCACCAUGCAGUGCAAGUCCCGCAGUCUGACACCAUCUUGGCAAUUCAGGCUGAUGGGACAGUGGCAGGUCUGCACACUGGGGAUGCUACAAUUGACCCUGACACCAUCAGUGCUUUGGAACAGUAUGCAGCAAAGGUGUCCAUUGAUGGAAGUGAAAGUGUAGCAGGUACUGGAAUGAUUGGAGAAAAUGAGCAAGAGAAAAAAAUGCAGAUUGUUUUACAAGGACAUGCUACAAGAGUAACUGCUAAAUCUCAACAGAGUGGAGAGAAGGCAUUUCGAUGUGAAUAUGAUGGAUGUGGAAAAUUAUAUACAACAGCUCAUCAUCUCAAGGUCCAUGAGAGGUCACACACAGGAGAUCGGCCUUAUCAGUGUGAGCAUGCAGGCUGUGGGAAGGCAUUUGCAACAGGUUAUGGAUUAAAAAGUCACGUCAGAACUCAUACAGGAGAAAAGCCAUAUCGGUGUUCGGAAGAUAAUUGUACUAAAUCUUUCAAAACUUCAGGAGAUCUACAGAAACACAUCAGAACUCAUACAGGAGAAAGGCCCUUUAAGUGUCCCUUCGAAGGCUGCGGUCGGUCCUUUACAACAUCAAAUAUCAGAAAAGUGCACGUUAGGACACACACAGGAGAAAGACCUUAUUACUGCACAGAGCCAGGAUGUGGGAGGGCAUUUGCCAGUGCAACAAAUUAUAAAAACCAUGUGAGGAUACACACAGGAGAAAAGCCAUAUGUUUGUACAGUUCCUGGGUGUGACAAAAGGUUUACAGAAUAUUCCAGUUUGUACAAACAUCAUGUUGUCCACACUCAUUCCAAACCUUACAACUGUAACCACUGUGGGAAGACAUACAAGCAGAUCUCCACGCUGGCCAUGCACAAACGGACAGCCCACAACGACACUGAGCCCAUCGAGGAGGAGCAGGAAGCCUUCUUUGAGCCGCCCCCAGGUCAAGGUGAAGAUGUUCUUAAAGGGUCCCAGAUUACGUAUGUUACAGGUGUAGAAGGGGACGACGUUGUUUCUACACAAGUAGCCACAGUAACCCAAUCUGGACUGAGUCAACAAGUUACACUCAUAUCCCAGGAUGGGACUCAGCAUGUCAACAUAUCUCAAGCUGACAUGCAGGCCAUUGGCAACACCAUCACAAUGGUAACGCAGGAUGGCACGCCCAUCACAGUCCCCGCCCAUGAUGCAGUCAUCUCCUCAGCAGGAACGCACUCUGUUGCUAUGGUUACUGCUGAGGGUACAGAAGGGGAACAGGUUGCAAUUGUAGCUCAAGACUUGGCAGCAUUCCAUACUGCCUCAUCAGAAAUGGGGCACCAGCAGCAUAGCCAUCACUUAGUAACCACAGAAACCAGACCUCUGACCUUAGUAGCAACAUCCAAUGGCACCCAGAUUGCAGUUCAGCUUGGAGAACAGCCAUCUCUGGAAGAAGCCAUCAGAAUAGCGUCUAGAAUCCAACAAGGAGAAACGCCAGGGUUGGAUGAUUAAUCCUCAGAACAAUGGAGCAAUAAAGCAGAAGGAGUCUUUCAUCUUCUGGCAGCAGAAAUCCAUGAAGCCCGGGCCCAGGAAAAUUAGAAGUUUUCCAUUCCUGAUACACUGUACACAUUUUUAUGCGAGAGUGGAGAACAUUUUAUUCUUGACACUUUUGUGUAUAUAACCCUUGGAAUAGAUUCUCAGAGUGAUUCAUUGUGUACAAGGAAGUAUGAAAUUAGGGCAAUACAGUAAAUUUUCAUGUUACUCUUUUAUCAGAUCACAAACUCCUAGAGUCUACAUGCAAGACUAGUAAAGUCUUAUGGAGUCUUAUGAUGGAUUUUUAACUUCCCGUGGAAAAAAAAAUAAAGGCUGUAUCUAAAAUAUCAAAGGUUCUAUAUGUCACACAAUCGUAAUUCCAAAAGCCAUUAUGGAUAAUAAAGGGUGUAAAGCCUUCAGAUAUUUCCCCAGUUAGUAGAGUGUCUGCGGUUUUUGUUCUACUAUAUGCUUGUCCAUUUUUAUUUGUAUCUCAUGGUUUGCAGACUGUUUGAAUAAUUUAUAGUUUCCCAUCCCUGUUAAAAACCAGCUCUUCAAGCUGAAAUGCUAAUUAUAUUGGCAUUACAUUGAAUUAUGUACAAAAUUAUAAAAUUUGGUUAUUUAAAAUUAAAAAGUUAAAUCCAGUGGUUUUGUUAAAGAUUUUGCUUAGUAUUCAAUUUUUAUUACUGUUUUUUAAAAAUAAUGAAUCAUCAAAGUUUAACCACAGGCUGGUGCCCGGGAUAACAGUACUGUAAUUGGAAAUGGCUUUACUCUGAAAAUUAGGUUAGUGGGUUGGUGUAAAUUAUUUAUUUUUGCUUAUGUACUUUUGUUUUAAAGCUUAUUUACCCCAAAGUUUAUUAUUAAUUUUGAAUACAGCAAUUUUUAAAAUGUUA